AGUCCCCACUGCUCAGCACUAGGCCGGCAGAAUCUGAGCGAUGUCUUCCACACUCCCUGCCCUGCUCUGCGUCGGGCUGUGUCUGAGUCAGAGGAUCAGCGCCCAGCAGCAGACUCUCCCAAAACCGUUCAUCUGGGCCGAGCCCCAUUUCAUGGUUCCAAAGGAAAAGCAAGUGACCAUCUGUUGCCAGGGAAAUUAUGGGGCUGUUGAAUACCAGCUGCACUUUGAAGGAAGCCUUUUUGCCGUGGACAGACCAAAACCCCCUGAGCGGAUUAACAAAGUCAAAUUCUACAUCCCGGACAUGAACUCCCGCAUGGCAGGGCAAUACAGCUGCAUCUAUCGGGUUGGGGAGCUCUGGUCAGAGCCCAGCAACUUGCUGGAUCUGGUGGUAACAGAAAUGUAUGACACACCCACCCUCUCGGUUCAUCCUGGACCCGAAGUGAUCUCGGGAGAGAAGGUGACCUUCUACUGCCGUCUAGACACUGCAACAAGCAUGUUCUUACUGCUCAAGGAGGGAAGAUCCAGCCACGUACAGCGCGGAUACGGGAAGGUCCAGGCGGAGUUCCCCCUGGGCCCUGUGACCACAGCCCACCGAGGGACAUACCGAUGUUUUGGCUCCUAUAACAACCAUGCCUGGUCUUUCCCCAGUGAGCCAGUGAAGCUCCUGGUCACAGGCGACAUUGAGAACACCAGCCUUGCACCUGAAGACCCCACCUUUCCUGAAACUUGAGGUUGCUGUUUGAGCUGAAGAGAGAGCAGAAAUCUGUCCAGAGGCGAAGAGAGCGAAGAUCCUGCCGAGCCCAGUUCGGAAUGGUUAGGUAAGUGCACCUGCAGGAGAACACACGUUCAUCUCUUAGGACUAGUACCUGCAUGGUGAGAUGGGCAUCUGCAAACCACAUUUCAAUGGCAAAAACCACAAUUACUUUUGCACCAACCUAAAACAGUGUCUAUAGUAAACAAUAUUGCAUCACAUGCUUUGCUACCAGUAUAGAUCUUAAGUUUUACAAAAAAAAUAAAAUAAUAGAUAAGGCUGAGUGAGGUGGCUCAUGCCUGUAAUCCCAACACUUUGCUAGGCCAAAGUGGGAAGAUCACUUGAGCCCAGGAGUUUAAGACCAACUUGGGCUAGAAACUGAGACCCCCAUCUCUACAAAAAAAUAAAAUAAUUAACCGGGCAAGGUGGUGCACGCCCAUAGUCCCAGCUACUCGGGAGGCUGAGGCAGGAGAAUCACUUGAACCCGGGAGGCGGAGGUUGCAGUGAGCCAAGAUCGCGCCACUGCACUCCAGCCUGGGGGACAGAGCGAGACUCCGUCUCAAAAAUAAAAAGCCCCAAUUCCUAAUUGCCAAGUCGUGUCUCCACGUUGAACAUGAAGCUGGAAAGAAGUCCAGCCAGAGGGAAAUUCUGACAGUAAGCGACAGGGCAAAGGAGACGCUGGCCUCUUCCUAGUGGAGCGUGGGAUGGGAAAACAGUUCUUACCUUUCAAAUUCAAUGUCCAGUUCAAAAUCCAUGUAAUUCUCCAGGAACACCCCCUUUGCU